ACACCUGACUACCGCUGCGCCCCGAGCGGCCACGGCCGCCGCGGCACCUCCACUGCCCGCGCUCGCGGUGUGUCGCACUCAGCCAACACGCAGCCAAAUCCCGGCCCCGCCGCUCGCUCUCCGGGUAGCGGUCCAGGGGAGAGGGCCGGCAGCCUCGGCAGCGGGCGGGGAUACCAGAUCCGCCAGGGAGGUGCCGCAGCUCCGCUUCAACUCCUGGCAGGGAGAGGAGGAAGCGGCGGCGCAGGAGGGCAGCGGCGAGGCUCGGCGCUGGGGAGCCGGGAGGGGUGGAGCGUGAGGAUCCGCGGCCGGUAGAGAGGGGCGCACUAGGCAGAGGGGUGGGCAGGACCGGCAAGGAGUACAGGACUUCGGGGACAAACGCAAGACCGCGCGGGCAGCAGGGGCGUGGGAAGACGGGGAGGGGACCAAGGUGCAGGAUCUGGGGCUAGAAGGACAGACAGCCGGCCCCGAGUGCUGAGGAGGGCGGGCGCCCAGUGGUGUCGAGGGCGACUUGGGGCGCGCGGCGGCAGGCAGCGGGGAAGCCGCCGCGAGGGCGUCCAGCAGGGCUCAGCGCGGCGCUCAAGUUCGGGGCUGGGAGCUCUGAAUCCGAACAGCCCAGCGUGGGCAGAGGUCGUGCGCUGCGCGUACGGGAGACCGGGGAGAGGAAUCGCCGGGAAAAGCAAAUGGAGGGUGAAACUUGUGCGCCUGCCGGGGGGAGGGGAGCAGCAGGCGAGUGCGGGCAGGAACACGAGGCGGGGCAGGAAAGCCGCGGCGGCCGCGAGGCGCUGGGGACGCGGCAGCGGGAGGGAGGCCCCCGGCCCCCGGCGCGCAGGUCCUGGCCCUGGCGCGUGUUCGGGGCGAGGGCCGAGGGUCUCGUGGGCAGGAGUCUCCGCGCCCUCCCGCGAGCCCACACACUUACUUUCCAGCUUAGGCAGCGGCCGUCGUCGCUCCAGGGAUCAGGGACAUCGGCGCCGAGGGGUCGCCGCUGCGGCACCCGAAAAAAUUAA